AGUCACUGCCGCGGCGCCUUGAGUCUCCGGGCCGCCUUGCCAUGGCUGCCCGUGGUGUCAUCGCUCCAGUUGGCGAGAGUUUGCGCUACGCUGAGUACUUGCAGCCCUCGGCCAAACGGCCAGACGCCGACGUCGACCAGCAGAGACUGGUAAGAAGUUUGAUAGCUGUAGGACUGGGUGUUGCAGCUCUUGCAUUUGCAGGUCGCUACGCAUUUCGGAUCUGGAAACCUCUAGAACAAGUUAUCACAGAAACUGCAAAGAAGAUUUCAACUCCUAGCUUUUCAUCCUACUAUAAAGGAGGAUUUGAACAGAAAAUGAGUAGGCGAGAAGCUGGUCUUAUUUUAGGUGUAAGCCCAUCUGCUGGCAAGGCUAAGAUUAGAACAGCUCAUAGGAGAGUCAUGAUUUUGAAUCACCCAGAUAAAGGUGGAUCUCCUUACGUAGCAGCCAAAAUAAAUGAAGCAAAAGACUUGCUAGAAACAACCACCAAACAUUGAUGCUUAAGGACCACACUGAAGGAAAAAAAAAGAGGGGACUUCGAAAAAAAAAAAAGCCCUGCAAAAUAUUCUAAAACAUGGUCUUCUUAAUUUUCUAUAUGGAUUGACCACAGUCUUAUCUUCCACCAUUAAGCUGUAUAACAAUAAAAUGUUAAUAGUCUUGCUUUUUAUUAUCUUUUAAAGAUCUCCUUAAAUUCUAUAACUGAUCUUUUUUCUUAUUUUGUUUGUGACAUUCAUACAUUUUUAAGAUUUUUGUUAUGUUCUGAAUUCCCCCCUACACACACACACACACACACACACACACACACGUGCAAAAAAUAUGAUCAAGAAUGCAAUUGGGAUUUGUGAGCAAUGAGUAGACCUCUUAUUGUUUAUAUUUGUACCCUCAUUGUCAAUUUUUUUUUAGGGAAUUUGGGACUCUGCCUAUAUAAGGUGUUUUAAAUGUCUUGAGAACAAGCACUGGCUGAUACCUCUUGGAGAUAUGAUCUGAAAUGUAAUGGAAUUUAUUAAAUGGUGUUUAGUAAAGUAGGGGUUAAGGACUUGUUAAAGAACCCCACUAUCUCUGAGACCCUAUAGCCAAAGCAUGAGGACUUGGAGAGCUACUAAAAUGAUUCAGGUUUACAAAAUGAGCCCUGUGAGGAAAGGUUGAGAGAAGUCUGAGGAGUUUGUAUUUAAUUAUAGUCUUCCAGUACUGUAUAUUCAUUCAUUACUCAUUCUACAAAUAUUUAUUGACCCCUUUUGAUGUGCAAGGCACUAUCGUGCGUCCCCUGAGAGUUGCAAGUAUGAAGCAGUCAUGGAUCAUGAACCAAAGGAACUUAUAUGUAGAGGAAGGAUAAAUCACAAAUAGUGAAUACUGUUAGAUACAGAUGAUAUAUUUUAAAAGUUCAAAGGAAGAAAAGAAUGUGUUAAACACUGCAUGAGAGGAGGAAUAAGUGGCAUAGAGCUAGGCUUUAGAAAAGAAAAAUAUUCCGAUACCAUAUGAUUGGUGAGGUAAGUGUUAUUCUGAGAUGAGAAUUAGCAGAAAUAGAUAUAUCAAUCGGAGUGAUUAGAGUGCAGGGUUUCUGGAAAGCAAGGUUUGGACAGAGUGGUCAUCAAAGGCCAGCCCUGUGACUUACACUGCAUUAAAUUAAUUUCUUAGAACAUAGUCCCUGAUCAUUAUCACUUUACUAUUCCAAAGGUGAGAGAACAGAUUCAGAUAGAGUGCCAGCAUUGUUUCCCAGUAUUCCUUUACAAAUCUUGGGUUCAUUCCAGGUAAACUGAACUACUGCAUUGUUUCUAUCUUAAAAUACUUUUUAGAUAUCCUAGAUGCAUCUUUCAACUUCUAACAUUCUGUAGUUUAGGAGUUCUCAACCUUGGCAUUAUUGACAUGUUAGGCCAAAUAAUUUUUUUUGUGGGAGGUCUCUUGUGCGUUUUAGAUGAUUAGCAAUAAUCCCUGACCUGUUAUCUACUAAAGACUAGUCGUUUCUCAUCAGUUGUGACAACAAAAAUGGUUCCAGAUAUUGCCAAAUGCCCUUUAGAGGACAGUAAUCGCCCCCAGUUGAGAACCAUUUCAGUAAAACUUUAAUUACUAUUUUUUCUUUUGGUUUAUAAAAUAAUGAUCCUGAAUUAAAUUGAUGGAACCUUGAAGUCGAUAAAAUAUAUUUCUUGCUUUAAAGUCCCCAUACGUGUCCUACUAAUUUUCUCAUGCUUUAGUGUUUUCACUUUUCUCCUGUUAUCCUUGUACCUAAGAAUGCCAUCCCAAUCCCCAGAUGUCCACCUGCCCAAAGUCUAGGCAUAGCUGAAGGCCAAGCUAAAAUGUAUCCCUCUUUUUCUGGUACAUGCAGCAAAAGUAAUAUGAAUUAUCAGCUUUCUGAGAGCAGGCAUUGUAUCUGUCUUGUUUGGUGUUACAUUGGCACCCAAUAAAUAUUUGUUGAGUGAAUGAAUAAAUUCCCAUAGCACUUUAUUCUUCACAUGGUACAUAACUAUAGGGGCUAUAGCUUGGUACCUUGUGAAGCAACUCUUGGUGUAACAUACCUUAUUUCUCAUACUAAAAUGCAAGAACCUUUAGAGCAAGGAUCUUGCCAUUCAUCUUUGUAACCUCUUUACUCUGGAGCACUUGCAUUUAGCAGGCAUCAUAAAGUUUUACGUACCAAGAAAAUGUUGCUGUUUUCUGAAUACUAUGCAUCAAAAAAUGUUACCACUAAUUUUUAAAGCUCUGCUAAGGAAUAUUGGGGCACCCUCAGAUGCACCUUUUAAUUGAUGUCAUAUUUUCCUAAUCCAUACUUUAUUCAUGAGAAUUUGAGUCACCCCAGCAUUAGCUUGGAAUUUCCUUAUUUCCCAUUUGCUUUGCAGGUGCCUUGGAGUCAGAUCUGGUUUUGAAUACUAUCUUCCUGUUAUGUGAUCUUGGGCAGUUACUUAAUUUUCUAGUCAAUAACCCGUAUCUAUAAAAUAGAGAAAAUAAUCCUACACACCGGGGCCUGUUGUGGGGCGGGGAGAGGGGGGAGGGAUCGCAUUUGGAGAUAUACUAAUGUAAAUGACAAGUUAAUUGGUGCAGCACACCAACAUGGCUCAUGUCUACAUAUGUAACAAACCUGCACGUUGUGCACAUGUGCCCUAGAACUUAAAGUAUAAUAAAAAGAAAUUUUAAAAAAUCCUGUCAAAUAAGGUUAUAGUAGAGAAUAAGGAUGUGUAAAGCAUUUAGUCACGUAAAUGCUUAAAAAAAUGUAAUUUUUACUUCUUUCACUGCCUCAUUUAAUUAGUUUUAUCUUUAAUAAUACCUUGGAUUCAGGGUAAAGUUUCAGUUAUGUCCCAGUAAUCAUUUAUUUUACCCUCGAAUCUGCAAUUUGGAUAGAACAUGGUGGGGACAGCUCGUCUCUAUUCCUUGCAGCAUUAACAGGCUGGAGGCACCACUUCUCUGGCCAGCAAGUUGGGCCUGGUUGUUGGCUGAGAGCCUCAGUUCCUUUCUGCACAGGUUCCUCUUUACAUAGGCUUCUCAACAGGGCUACUAGAGCAUCGUCACCAUAGCAGCUGUCUUAUAACAGAGAGUGGUCGGUCUGAGAGACAAAAAAUGGAAGCUGCCAAAUUGUUCUGGGUCUGGAAACUGUCAGGGCAUCACUUGUGCCAUAUUCAGUUGGCCUAAGAAUUACAGAGCCUGCCUCGAUUCAAAGGGAGAGGAUAGAGAGGACUGAAGGAAUCAGUGCUCAUCUUUAAUAUGCAGCAGGACAGGUUUGGGAUUUUUUUUCCCCCUUGAGUCUGUGAAGGCAUUACUUAAGAACAAAGUCAGGCAUGUAUAAUUGAACUACAGUUACUUGAAAUAUAAGCCCAGAAAGUUUCAGAUAAUAAAUACAACUAUUUUUCUGCUGUUACCCUUGUACCUAAAGAUGCCAUCCUAAUCCCCAGAUCUCCACAACUAUACCUACAUAGUAGAAGGUUAAAAUGUAUCCCUCUUUUUCUGGUGCAUCCAGCAAAAGUAAUAUCAUGAAUUAUGAGCUCUCUGAGAGCAAGGAUCAUAUCAGUCUUGUUUAUUGUUGCAGUGAACAAGUACAGUUGCAGAUAUUCAGGAGUAAUUAUCUAAAUGGCAGUAGGCUUAUAAAACUGAAUUUUCACCAGCCACACCCUCCCCCCAACUCCUUAUCUGUAAAAAGCUUAUUUGAGUGGUUACCUGUCUUCAGUAAAGAUUGCGCUUGCAUAUUUGCUGUCAUUGCAUAUUCUGCUUAAUUAAGCUCUGUUGAUAUUGCAGUUUCUGUGCAUACUUACAUCUUAGAUGCAAUCUGAGGGCCUAGGAAGGCCUUUUAAAAAUAAAACAAUUCCGAUUGCAGAGAAAGUGUAAGUCAAGGACAGUUAAUUCAAGGGGAACAUAGAAAGCUAUUUAGAUUUUAGUUGAUGGUGCCAGUCUUCAGCGUAAAGUCAAAAGUGGAGGGAAGUUUAGUAAGGAAAAAAUGUUGGGCUUGGAAUACAUUGUUUAGUCUUCAAAGCACUUUACUUUUUAUGAAAUAUAUUUUAGACAUUCAGCAAAUAUUGAAUACUUACUAUAUCAGGCAGUAAAGAUAUAAAUUCAUUCUUAAAAUGUGCAACAUGUUCAAACUGAAAAAAAUACAUUCUUAAACAGGAAACUUUUUCCUUCAUACUUUUUAAUUAACAAGACAUAUAAGAGUUGCAUUAAUGGGCGUGCUUAUGAUUGAUCACCCAGCAGCAUCAUUAGAAAUAAUAUAUUUUAUUCAUGUGCAGAAAUCUUUUGGUUGUCCUGGGGAACCUUGAACACAGAAAAGAGCUUUUAUUGAUAAGGUAAUUGAACACACUUGACAAUUAGCUUAAUAUGGUUUAAUACCAUUUGUGGGAGAAGAUGAAUCAGCCAGGCUCUUUACGUCAAGAAUAUGAAGUUUCUCUUGAGUCAACCAACUUAAGAUGAGCUACGGAGACUGCAGUGAAAAGUUAAAUAUCCAAGUACACCAGCCAAUUUCACACAGUGGAACCAUGCUGUCCUCGGGCACCCUGCACCUCGCCCAACAGUCAUCAACUAGAUGGAGGCUCCUGGCUGCAAGGAGGAUUUGAUGGGAAUGAGUAAAUGUGUCAGCAUAGUCCGUCCCUUCUAAUGGAAAAGCAACCCAAAGAGCAAAUCCUAUUAAUGGCUGGAUCAGUAUCAUCUACUUGUCAAAAACAUUCCAUGAAUUAUGAGUCAAAAUUUUAUUUAUGGUGGCAUUACACACAUUAAGAGAUGAGGACUUCUGUUAGCAUAAUUUAUUAGCUGGAAAAGUUGAGAAGGUUCUCUGGACUCAUUUUUAUAGGUGGAACCUAAGUGAUCUGGAUAAUUGCCCACCAGCAAAAUUGCUGGGCAUGGUGGACAAAGAAAAUGUUCCUUCUAAUGAUUUUUUAUGAGCUGAGUAGCUAUUGUUCCCAGCUGAGUGCUCUUUUCCUCUUUUUAUUGUUGCUGAGCAAAAGAAUUUAUAAAAAGCUCUUUCUUUUGUAUUAAAAACCCUGCUCAAUUGAAAUGCAAGUUCAUUAAGUAAUCUUCAUUUCUCUUCCUGCCAUAAUAACCCUUUCCCUCUCUGUUCGAUUCAACAGUAUCUAGCAGCACUGCUCCAAAUUUUAAGUCUGAACAGACUAUAUUACAUAGAUGUAGAGAAAUACUCAAUCUUCAGCAUUAAGAGGGAGCUUAAUUUCACACGGGUGGAAUAUGAUCACUCAGGCUAGAUGUUGGCCAUAAAUUUCAAAUUAGUAUCUCAACUUAGCAGGGGGGAUCAACAGUGGCAAACUUCAAUUAUGACAGGAUAAAAAUCACAUAGAGAUAUUGGUUCAAUAUGGACAUCUAAACUAUAAUGCUAAAAGCCAAUAAUUAGAAUAAGUUCAUUUUAAGAAAAGCAUUAAUAAUAUUAGCUAACGUUUAGUACCUGUGCCAAACAUUCUACCUAUGUUACCUUGAUUUUCAUAGCCAGCCUAAGAGGUACUAUUAUGUAUCCCCAUUUUACAGGUUAAGAAACAGGCUCAGAGGAGUUUAGGAUCUUUUCCAAGAUUACAUAGCCAGUAAGUGGUGGCACUAGGAACCAAAUUCAGACUCUGAAUCGCAUGCUGUUUAUAUUAUAUUGCACUCAUUCUAAAUAUGUGGGAAUCAGAAUGAAGGGGCUUGUAUGACUUUUGGCUCAUUUUUUGAUGCAUGUGACCUGGGAUUAUAAAUGUGAAAUUAGGUUUACGAAAGGAUCCAGUGUCAUUGUGCAUCAUGGGCAAGGAGUACCUAAUCUCUUUAAUUCUUCCCUGGAAGCUUACGAUGUCCAUCCAAGUGCACAUAGCAAAAGUUCUGUUGUAAAGUUUAGCAGAGUGACUUUCUUUGACUCAGAGUGAUGACGGAGGAAGCUUUGAUAAGAUUUUAUCUGAAAUGUUCAUGGACAAGAGCUUUCAAGGAGAACAUCCAGAGCAAGGUUCUGAAGACAGCUCAUGAAGGUGAAGCAGCAGACCUGGCACAAGAAAUGAAGAGAGAGCUCAGUGUAUUAAAGAUGAAAACAAGAAAACCGAAUAUAUUGAAAGGAGCAGAGAGGCAAUGAAAACAAGACAACUGAAAUGAGGUAACUUGCAGCAAUUGAAAGGGAAUUUCAGUACUUUUAUAGAAUUCUUAAAAAUUGUUUCCUGCUGUUUAUUUUCAAUUUUGAACAGGGUUAUUUGUCCAUGCCAUACUUUUUUUGCCAAAUUCCAAAAUUGUGUAUAGUUCUAUAGUUGUCUGGUGGAGUCAAUGGAACUUUAGUUACCAGUCUAAGAAUGUGUCUUUGAGAUUGUCCAGUUAAUUCUCUAUUUCCAGUAGCUGUAAUAAAUGGUGAAAAGGUUUCUGACUCCUGGAGAAAGUUUCUAACUCCUUAUGACUAAUAUUCAUAACAGACUUGUGAGUUCCUUGAACAUGGAUACACCUAUAUGCAAGAGUGUAUUCCAAAGCUAACUCAGUGAUCUUUCCAUUUAUCUAUUCUUGGAUUAGUGGUGCCUUUGCUCUUUCCUUCUGUAAAUGUGAAUAGUUAAGAGUUGACUGCAGAAGUGUUUACACUUUGGCUUCCAUGCCUCUGGAAUGUUUGUGCUUUGGUGGUGAGAUGUGAGACUAUAUUUGUAUAGUCUGCAUCUCUCAGGCUGCCCCAGAAUGUUGUACAGUGCAGUGCUGAAGAAAGCAGCAGGUACACACAGAAAUGCAGCCUUUCCUGGUUAACCCUGCUUGGAUCUGAGUUACACUUUGUUUCCUGACUUCUUGGGACUUAGGUAAUCAGUUUGCCUUCUACUCUAUCUCAUUUUGUACUCGCUUACAUACUACAUUCUUGUUUGGGCUUUCGUUUCUUCUUGUAAGCAGAGAUUUUUUAAAAUCCAAUAUGUGAAAAUACGGAUGCACUACAAUUAAAUAAAUAAAAUGCUGUUGUGUUUGUUUUGCUUUAAAAUUGUAAAGGAUAAACAAUAAGAUAGUUUUAUCUAUGUGGUUUUCCCGAUGCAGUUAAAAUAAAACCUAAUCUGCUAAAAUUGAA